CUUCCUCUCCUGGGCCGUCCUCUGAGCAGCAGACGGGGCUAAGCGUUCCCCAGCUCGCCUUCACACACAGCCCGUGCCACCACACCGACGGUACCAUGAAGGACGAGGUAGCUCUACUGGCUGCUGUCACCCUCCUGGGAGUCCUGCUGCAAGCCUACUUCUCCCUGCAGGUGAUCUCGGCGCGCAGGGCCUUCCGCGUGUCGCCGCCGCUCACCACCGGCCCACCCGAGUUCGAGCGCGUCUACCGAGCCCAGGUGAACUGCAGCGAGUACUUCCCGCUGUUCCUCGCCACGCUCUGGGUCGCCGGCAUCUUCUUUCAUGAAGGGGCGGCGGCCCUGUGCGGCCUGGUCUACCUGUUCGCGCGCCUCCGCUACUUCCAGGGCUACGCGCGCUCCGCGCAGCUCAGGCUGGCACCGCUGUACGCGAGCGCGCGCGCCCUCUGGCUGCUGGUGGCGCUGGCUGCGCUCGGCCUGCUCGCCCACUUCCUCCCGGCCGCGCUGCGCGCCGCGCUCCUCGGACGGCUCCGGACGCUGCUGCCGUGGGCCUGAGACCAAGGCCCCCGGGCCGACGGAGCCGGGAAAGAAGAGCCGGAGCCUCCAGCUGCCCCGGGGAGGGGCGCUCGCUUCCGCAUCCUAGUCUCUAUCAUUAAAGUUCUAGUGACCGAGACCCGGGCUGCGUUCUCUGGGUCCGCGGGGGUGGCGCACCGCGGGCUACGGAGCCUGGAGGGGCCCAGCCCGAGUCCGGGCAGCCCGGGGCGGGCUUCCUAGUGGCGGCGUGAGAGUGGCUGCGAAGGAACGAGCC